GCCGCCGCCGCCCUUCGCGCCCUGGGCCAUCUCCCUCCCACCUCCCUCCGCGGAGCAGCCAGACAGCGAGGGCCCCGGCCGGGGGCAGGGGGGACGCCCCGUCCGGGGCACCCCCCCGGCUCUGAGCCGCCCGCGGGGCCGGCCUCGGCCCGGAGCGGAGGAAGGAGUCGCCGAGGAGCAGCCUGAGGCCCCAGAGUCUGAGACGAGCCGCCGCCGCCCCCGCCACUGCGGGGAGGAGGGGGAGGAGGAGCGGGAGGAGGGACGAGCUGGUCGGGAGAAGAGGAAAAAAACUUUUGAGACUUUUCCGUUGCCGCUGGGAGCCGGAGGCGCGGGGACCUCUUGGCGCGACGCUGCCCCGCGAGGAGGCAGGACUUGGGGACCCCAGACCGCCUCCCUUUGCCGCCGGGGACGCUUGCUCCCUCCCUGCCCCCUACACGGCGUCCCUCAGGCGCCCCCAUUCCGGACCAGCCCUCGGGAGUCGCCGACCCGGCCUCCCGCAAAGACUUUUCCCCAGACCUCGGGCGCACCCCCUGCACGCCGCCUUCAUCCCCGGCCUGUCUCCUGAGCCCCCGCGCAUCCUAGACCCUUUCUCCUCCAGGAGACGGAUCUCUCUCCGACCUGCCACAGAUCCCCUAUUCAAGACCACCCACCUUCUGGUACCAGAUCGCGCCCAUCUAGGUUAUUUCCGUGGGAUACUGAGACACCCCCGGUCCAAGCCUCCCCUCCACCACUGCGCCCUUCUCCCUGAGGACCUCAGCUUUCCCUCGAGGCCCUCCUACCUUUUGCCGGGAGACCCCCAGCCCCUGCAGGGGCGGGGCCUCCCCACCACACCAGCCCUGUUCGCGCUCUCGGCAGUGCCGGGGGGCGCCGCCUCCCCCAUGCCGCCCUCCGGGCUGCGGCUGCUGCCGCUGCUGCUACCGCUGCUGUGGCUACUGGUGCUGACGCCUGGCCGGCCGGCCGCGGGACUAUCCACCUGCAAGACUAUCGACAUGGAGCUGGUGAAGCGGAAGCGCAUCGAGGCCAUCCGCGGCCAGAUCCUGUCCAAGCUGCGGCUCGCCAGCCCCCCGAGCCAGGGGGAGGUGCCGCCCGGCCCGCUGCCCGAGGCCGUGCUCGCCCUGUACAACAGCACCCGCGACCGGGUGGCCGGGGAGAGUGCAGAACCGGAGCCCGAGCCUGAGGCCGACUACUACGCCAAGGAGGUCACCCGCGUGCUAAUGGUGGAAACCCACAACGAAAUCUAUGACAAGUUCAAGCAGAGUACACACAGCAUAUAUAUGUUCUUCAACACAUCAGAGCUCCGAGAAGCGGUACCUGAACCCGUGUUGCUCUCCCGGGCAGAGCUGCGUCUGCUGAGGCUCAAGUUAAAAGUGGAGCAGCACGUGGAGCUGUACCAGAAAUACAGCAACAAUUCCUGGCGAUACCUCAGCAACCGGCUGCUGGCACCCAGCGACUCGCCAGAGUGGUUAUCUUUUGAUGUCACCGGAGUUGUGCGGCAGUGGUUGAGCCGUGGAGGGGAAAUUGAGGGCUUUCGCCUUAGCGCCCACUGCUCCUGUGACAGCAGGGAUAACACACUGCAAGUGGACAUCAACGCAGGGUUCACUACCGGCCGCCGAGGUGACCUGGCCACCAUUCAUGGCAUGAACCGGCCUUUCCUGCUUCUCAUGGCCACCCCGCUGGAGAGGGCCCAGCAUCUGCAAAGCUCCCGGCACCGCCGAGCCCUGGACACCAACUAUUGCUUCAGCUCCACGGAGAAGAACUGCUGCGUGCGGCAGCUGUACAUUGACUUCCGCAAGGACCUCGGCUGGAAGUGGAUCCACGAGCCCAAGGGCUACCAUGCCAACUUCUGCCUCGGGCCCUGCCCCUACAUUUGGAGCCUGGACACGCAGUACAGCAAGGUCCUGGCCCUGUACAACCAGCAUAACCCGGGCGCCUCGGCGGCGCCGUGCUGCGUGCCGCAGGCGCUGGAGCCGCUGCCCAUCGUGUACUACGUGGGCCGCAAGCCCAAGGUGGAGCAGCUGUCCAACAUGAUCGUGCGCUCCUGCAAGUGCAGCUGAGGUCCCGCCCCGCCCCGCCCCGCCCCGGCAGGCCCGGCCCCACCCCGCCCCGCCCCCGCUGCCUUGCCCAUGGGGGCUGUAUUUAAGGACACCCGUGCCCCAAGCCCACCUGGGGCCCCAUUAAAGAUGGAGAGAGGACUGCGGAUCUCUGUGUCAUUGGGCGCCUGCCUGGGGUCUCCAUCCCUGACGUUCCCCCACUCCCACUCCCUCUCUCUCCCUCUCUGCCUCCUCCUGCCUGUCUGCACUAUUCCUUUGCCCGGCAUCAAGGCACAGGGGACCAGUGGGGAACACUACUGUAGUUAGAUCUAUUUAUUGAGCACCUUGGGCACUGUUGAAGUGCCUUACAUUAAUGAACUCAUUCAGUCACCAUAGCAACACUCUGAGAUGCAGGGACUCUGAUAACACCCAUUUUAAAGGUGAGGAAACAAGCCCAGAGAGGUUAAGGGAGGAGUUCCUGCCCACCAGGAACCUGCUUUAGUGGGGGAUAGUGAAGAAGACAAUAAAAGAUAGUAGUUCAGGCCAGGCGGGGUGGCUCACGCCUGUAAUCCUAGCACUUUUGGGAGGCAGAGAUGGGAGGAUUACUUGAAUCCAGGCAUUUGAGACCAGCCUGGGUAACAUAGUGAGACCCUAUCUCUACAAAACACUUUUAAAAAAUGUACACCUGUGGUCCCAGCUACUCUGGAGGCUAAGGUGGGAGGAUCACUUGAUCCUGGGAGGUCAAGGCUGCAG